AAGGGACGAGGCGCUUCUCGUCCAGAGCCCAGGUAAUCCGGGCGGGAUCAGCGAGCGUCGCGAUGUGAUGACGUCAGGCCCCGGGCAGGCCGGGAGUGGCGUGCUGGGCGUGCGCGGCUGCGGUACGGCGUGUUGGUCCCAGCGGUUCAGCUGAGGUAGGGACGUGCUGUAGGCCGGAAUGUUACCGGCUGUUGGAUCUGCGGAUGAGGAGGAGGAUCCUGCGGAGGAGGAUUGUCCUGAAUUGGUUCCCAUGGAGACGACGCAAAGCGAGGAGGAGGAAAAGUCUGGCCUCGGCGCCAAGAUCCCAGUCACAAUUAUCACCGGGUAUUUAGUUAUUCAGAGGCUGCUCUGCUGAGAAGAUGAACAAAUUUCUUGUCCAAAACAAUGUAUUUCAAACGUGCCGCUCGGGCCUUUCCCGUAUUGCUCACUGGUGCUGGGAAGACAACACUUCUGAACUAUAUUUUGACAGAGCAACAUAGUAAAAGAGUAGCGGUCAUUUUAAAUGAAUUUGGGGAAGGAAGUGCGCUGGAGAAAUCCUUAGCUGUCAGCCAAGGUGGAGAGCUCUAUGAAGAGUGGCUGGAACUUAGAAACGGUUGCCUCUGCUGUUCAGUGAAGGACAAUGGCCUUAGAGCUAUUGAGAAUUUGAUGCAAAAGAAGGGGAAAUUUGAUUACAUACUGUUAGAGACCACUGGAUUGGCAGACCCAGGUGCAGUGGCUUCUAUGUUUUGGGUUGAUGCUGAAUUAGGGAGUGAUAUUUACCUUGAUGGUAUCAUAACUAUAGUGGAUUCAAAAUAUGGAUUAAAAGCAAAGAAUUGGACAACUUAAAAUGACAGCUCUCUAUUCUGAGGACUUGACACCCAGGCUACUGACAUUGUUCUUUUCGGUUCUACAAAUGUGACAGCAUUUAAUGCAAUAGAAGCAAUGAAUGAAGUUACCCAGAGAAGGUCAACAUUUAGCAGAAGAGAAACCUGAUGGCCUUAUCAAUGAAGCUACUAGGCAAGUUGCUUUGGCAGAUGCCAUUCUCAUUAAUAAAACAGACUUGGUUCCAGAAGAAGAUGUAAAGAAAUUAAGAGCGACAAUUAGAUCCAUAAAUGGACUAGGACAAAUCUUAGAAACACAAAGAUCAAGAGUUGAUCUCUCUAAUGUAUUAGAUCUUCAUGCCUUUGAUAGUCUCUCUGGAAUAAGUUUGCAGAAAAAACUUCAGCAUGUGCCAGGAACACAACCUCACCUUGAUCAGAGUAUUGUUACAAUCACAUUUGAAGUACCAGGAAAUGCAAAGGAAGAACAUCUUAAUAUGUUUAUUCAGAAUCUCCUGUGGGAAAAGAAUGUGAGAAACAAGGACAAUCACUGCAUGGAGGUCAUAAGGCUGAAGGGAUUGGUGUCAAUCAAAGACAAAUCACAACAAGUGAUUGUCCAGGGUGUCCAUGAGCUCUAUGAUCUGGAGGAGACUCCAGUGAGCUGGAAGGAUGACACUGAGAGAACAAAUCGAUUGGUCCUCCUUGGCAGAAAUUUAGAUAAGGAUAUCCUUAAACAGCUGUUUAUAGCUACUGUGACAGAAACAGAAAAGCAGUGGACAACACAUUUCAAAGAAGAUCAAGUUUGUACAUAACACUAGAGGCAUUUCUUAUCAAAAGGAUUGGAUAAUAAAAAUAAGUUUCUACUGGGUAUAUUUCAAGCAUUUAUUUAUUACUUUAGUUACGAAUUCCAAUAUACUUUAAAAUGGUAUUUGUUUUACAGCAUACAUAAAAUGUAGCAAAUCGGUACUGUAAAACAUUUAACAUUCAUACAGUUAUAUAUAAUAUCCUUUUUUUUAAAGAAUGGUAUUUCACAAAAAUGUCUUUUGAAAUUGGCUUUGGAGUUUACAUAUACUGAACAUGAAAGUUUAUAAUAAUGAUGAUACAACUUUCAACAUUGUCAUUUUUUCUUAGAACUUCAGCUGAUUGCAGAGAUAUAAUGAUUACAUUGUUAUUAAAUUUUUUUAACACAAGUAAGUGUCACCAUUUUAUGACAUGAAAUAAAAGGUUAUGACUGUUAUUGAUGUUGAUGUUGACGACCUGAUCACCUGGCUGA